AUUGAUUUUGAGACUGCCCUUUGUACCGAAUUCACUCGGGUCCCGUCAGCAUGAAGAUGGAAUUGGUUUACACUUCUUAGGCACUUAGAGCCUGUGGCAGGUGUAUACAUCAGACCGAGGCGCCGAAGGAUUUAGUUGGGGUCGCAGGCGCCUGCCCCUUCCCCGUUCGUCAGGGUGGGGGCGCGUCUAUGCGGCCUCCCCCGCGGGCCGACCCCGGGUGCUCUGAGGCGCCUAGGAGCCCUUCCCAGACCCCGGGGGGGAGGGCACGGCAGCUACGGGAGCCUUCCGGCUACCCCGCGUUUCGGGCUGCAGCCCAGAAGUUUGGAAGAUGUUUUCACAUUAACUUUGAGAGCGCACAAGUCUUCGUCUUCCUCCCCGCCGCCGCGGGAAGCGCUCGCCGCCUUUCCCCCGCGCUUCGCGGCUCAGUUCUGCGAGCCCCCAAGACCCGUUGGACGCUCCUCGGGAGGAUUUUUAGACUCUGAGGAGCAGUUGGAGCUAAUCCACAUUAUGGAAAUGGAAACCACCGAACCUGAGCCAGACUGUGUAGUGCAGCCUCCCUCUCCUCCUGAUGACUUUUCAUGCCAAAUGAGACUCUCUGAGAAGAUCACUCCAUUGAAGACUUGUUUUAAGAAAAAGGAUCAGAAAAGAUUGGGAACUGGAACCCUGAGGUCUUUGAGGCCAAUAUUAAACACUCUUCUAGAAUCUGGCUCACUUGAUGGGGUUUUUAGAUCUAGGAACCAGAGUACAGAUGAGAACAGCUUACAUGAACCUAUGAUGAAGAAAGCCAUGGAAAUCAAUUCAUCAUGCCCACCAGCAGAAAAUAAUAUGUCUGUUCUGAUUCCUGAUAGGACAAAUGUUGGGGACCAGAUACCGGAAGCCCAUCCUUCCACUGAAGCUCCAGAACGAGUGGUUCCAAUCCAAGAUCACAGCUUUCCAUCAGAAACCCUCAGUGGGACGGUGGCAGAUUCCACACCAGCUCACUUCCAGACUGAUCUUUUGCACCCAGUUUCAAGUGAUGUUCCUACUAGUCCUGACUGCUUAGACAAAGUCAUAGAUUAUGUUCCAGGCAUUUUCCAAGAAAACAGUUUUACAAUCCAAUACAUUCUGGACACCAGUGAUAAGCUGAGUACUGAGCUCUUUCAGGACAAAAGUGAAGAGGCUUCCCUUGACCUCGUGUUUGAGCUGGUGAACCAGUUGCAGUACCACACUCACCAAGAGAACGGAAUUGAAAUUUGCAUGGACUUUCUGCAAGGCACUUGUAUUUAUGGCAGGGAUUGUUUGAAGCACCACACUGUCUUGCCAUAUCAUUGGCAGAUCAAAAGGACAACUACUCAAAAGUGGCAGAGUGUAUUCAAUGAUUCUCAGGAGCACUUGGAAAGAUUUUACUGUAACCCAGAAAAUGAUAGAAUGAGAAUGAAGUAUGGAUUGCAAAACUUUGCAGAACAGCGGCUCCCACUUCACCUUCAUGAAGCAAAUUUCCAGUCUGCUGAGUACUUCAGCAUCUUGCGAUGUUGUGUUUCCUGGCAACAAGAUGCAGAUAACGGCAUGUUGAGCCUUGCUGAGAGAUUCACAAACAAGCUGGAGCAGCCCAGGUUCACAUGGUUACCACAUUAUUUGGCUAAAGCUAUUAAUCUCUGUGGUCAGGCCUGUAAAGCUGGUCUAUCUGUGCAGAUUGCGCAUAACCAGGAAGUGUGUGUUCAGCUGUGUAUAUGUCGAAGUUGGAACCAGCAGUCUUUGGAUUCAGAAAUAAUGAAUGGCAGUUGUUUAUCCCACUGUUUUCAGUAGUUUAUAUGGCUUGGUAAAUCAUUAUCAUAUUCUGUAUCCAUAACAUCUUCAUUGUGUGAUAUACUUGGGGAAAGUUCAUAGUUCUGGGUCUCUAGCAGAGAUGAAAGUUCAUAGUUUCAAACUGUACAGAUAAAAUCUUUUAUUUAGCUUUGCAAAUGUAUUGGAUUUAAUACCUAAAUCUAAAUUAUAUGUAUAGUGUUCAUUUUGUUCUCAGGAAUGAAAUUGGAAAGGAAGUUGAACUAGAUAAAUUCACAGGACCUUUCCAACUUUUUAGUCAAGAUGCUUAGAUACUAAAAGCACAUUAAAAAAGGAUUUCAAUAAUACAUGCUUAUUUGUUCCUUGUAAUGAAAUUAUGAUGUAAUCCCACUUUGCUUUCUCAUUUUGCUUUUGUACAUCUACAAACGUUCAUUGCCAACAUCAACUGCAUACUAGUGUGUAUGUACUUCCCAGAUAUAGAUGCUGAGGCUUCUUUUUUGCACACGAGAUGAGCCUUGGAGAAUUUCCAAAUUCCAAAUAUACAGUUGAGAAACAACAUUGAGUGUUGUGUUUUCGAUUAAGAAAACAGAGUCUGGAACAGUGUAGGCACUCAUCCUUAGUAGACGAUGACAUUGGAUGGCAGAAUUAAGCAGUUUUAAAAGAGCCUUGCACACUGUGGAGUACUGUUGUGGAUAAUUGAAAUUAUGGAGGUUGUGCAAAUCUCUCUUUAGCAAACAAGAUCACCACUAGUUUCAUAUUACAUUCAUUUUAAAUUGAGCCAGAACAAUUUUCUAUUUAUUUCCACCUGUCAAGAAGGGACACACUGCAAACCUUAUUUUGGAGGCUACCUGCAGGUGCACAUGUGACCAAUGAUUAUUUCUAAUUCUGAAUUUAUUGAAAGAGAGUGGAGGUGAAGAGGAAGAGGAAAGUUGCAAACCCUGAAUCCAUUAUUAAUUUUUUUCAGAGGACAGGGUUUUUUUCUUUUGGGAUUAAUGCUCACUGAUAAAAGAGGGAGCUUUAGUUGCUUUAAGGCUUAAGGCUAGAGUGUUGUCAUAGUUUUAGUUGCUGAGUGAUUUUGAUUGCUAAUUGCCCUUAGAAGUCUAUUUUUAAACUCUGUCCAAGGGACAAUACCAUUAGAUGACUUCACAGAAACUCUAUAUAAAAGAGAAAUGUAUAUUAAUGAUCAUAAAAAGCAUAUACUGUUACAGUCCCUAUAUGACUUGCAUAGUGAAUUAGCUAAACUAGAGCAAGCUCCUGACUGAACUCUACUGGAGUAGUUAAAUUAGCCAAGUUAGCUCUGGCGUGCACAGCUGUGAUGAUGUAUGAACUAACUCAUUAUGUGUUAUUGAUAACACUGGAGAGAGGAGAACAGCUGAAACUUACUAUGCCUUGUGACUUUUUGGUAGUUCUUGAAUAUACACAGCUGGAUGAGUUUAAAUUUAUUUUAAAAAUUUCUGCCUAAGAGAAAGACAGCUCCAUAAGCAAGAACUGUGUUUGAAGUGACUUUCAAAAUGUGUGCCUUGUGCUUUAGGAUAAAGCAAUCCAAUGAAUUAUUUUUUGUACUUCUUUAUGCUACUAUUUACAUAUGAAAUAAAACUAAUUGGCUUCUGUCUAUACUAACCCAGAGAAGUUACUGGAUCUGUGUAGAGCUGUCAUGGCAAUCAAUAGCAAUCAUUUAUUUAUUCCCUUUUUGGUUUUUCAUCAAUAAGCAGAUUAGACUUUUUGAAGCAGCUGCCACCUGGCUUCAGGUUGGGGUCAUUCUUUUCCUGAUGUAUUUAUGGUAAUGAAAAUGAACCUUGUCAAAAUGAUUUAUAACUUUUAAAUCAGACAGUUGGAGGAAAUAGCUUGUAAGGUUAUGUGGCAUUCCCUAAAAAUAAUUGCAUGAUACAUUAUAUAUUUUAUCAUUGAGUUGAAUCCAAAGCUCUUACUUUUUAUUGUAAGUAAGAAAAAAAAGGAAUACAAGUUGAAUAUCCCUUAUCCAAAAUUCUUGGAGACCAGAAGUGUUUCAGAUUUUGGAUUUUGGAAUAUUUGCAUAGUACCCCAGUUAAGCAUCUGAAAUCCGAAAUGCUCCAGUGAGCAUUUGGGUAUCAUCUUGGUGCUCAGAAAGUUUUGGGUUUGAAGCACUUCCGAUUUUCAGAUUUGGGGUGCUCAAUUUAUAGUAGUAACUCCAUUCAGCAUUUAAAAUUUCAUUCUGCACAUAGUGGGCAUGCAAAAAAAAAAAUGCUGACUUUUGACUGAUAACUCUGUUGUGUCCCUGUAAAUCUAUUUCCUAUUAUACUAGAAUUAUCCUAUUAUACUAGAAUUUCUAGAUCAUAGAUUUACAAUCUACCAUAAAGUAAAGAUAAACUUCAUAAGUUCUUCUGUGUAUUUCUAAUCAUGGUCAGUGAUCCUUAGUUUUAUUCUGGGUUUGGGUGCUAUUCCUAAAGGAUAAAGCAGUAUGUAGUCUAUGCAAACCUUGACUACUCAAGGAAUGCUACAAAAAUACAGCCAUUUGAGAUUAUGACUUUUUUCCCAUGGUCUCUUUUAUUUUUAUCUCCUGAUUUGAGACCACCAGAUUCUGCAUCCUUUGUCUGAUGGUGAUGAUUCUGGAUUGCAUUUAAAUUAGGACCUUAAGUCCUCUUAACCUUAGCCAACAACCUUUAAUAAUUAUCAGUCUCCAAUUUGUGAGUUGCAAUUGUCUUUUUGUGGAAGGAAAACUUAGUACAUGUGUAUAUCAUUUUUUGCAAAGGAAAAAACAUAUUUCAAAUUGCAAGAUAAUUAUUUUGGCACAACUUGUAUGGCUAGUUCAAAUUGGACACUGUAAAAGUUUUGAAAGAAACUCACUUUGUAAAAGUAGGAGAGUUUCUCUUUUAUAAUAAGAUUGGGGUCUUAAGGUAAAGUGAGUUCGAGAGAUUUUGUAUCUUUGAAAAAGACCACAGUGCUGAAGGUUAAGCCAUUUUCCCUUUGAUUCUGGGUUUGAAAUAGGUGAUAGCCUGAGAUCUUGAUUUUACCGCUACUUUGCAACACCUUAAACAGAAACUGUACAAGGAAUAAAAUACUUCUGAAGUUCACCAUUUCUAGGAGCAAACAAGCCACAUUUUAGAUGUGAAGGAAUUCCUUUUUUUUGAGACCAAGUUUCAGGCUGGAGUGCAGUGGCAUAAUCUCGGCUCCUGCAACCUCCGCCUCCUGGGUUCAAGCAAUUCUCCUGCCUCAGCCUUCCUGAGUAGCUGAGAUUACAGGCAUGCGCCACCAUGCCCAGCUAAUUUUGUAUUUUAGUAGAGACAGGGUUUCUCUAUGUUGGUCAGGCUCGUCUCGAACUCCCGACCUCAGAUGAUCCACCUGCCUCGGCCUCACAAAGUGCUAGGAUUACAGGCGUGAGCCACUGCGCCCAGUGAUGUGAAGGAAUUUCUUUAACAAAACUAAAUAGGGCUUAUUUUUAUAUUUAUAGAUUGUUUAUGACAGUGCUUUCUAGGGACUGAGAAUUAUACCGUAUACAGACUCACCCCAAUUUAAAAUUUCUUCCUUCAAACGUUAAACCUAAUCCACCUCAAUCCCUGACACAGUAACUGAAAGCUUCAAAUUUUUGAGAUUAAUUCACUUGUUAAUAGUGAAUUUGAAAUUACAAGUGGUAGGUUCUGAAAUACAUUUUGAAAUUUUUGAAAAUUAAGGAUUUUAUGUACAAUAAAUUCUGUUUGUAAAGAUUUAUAUUCAGUCUGUGAAGAGGACAGUAUUGCAGACUUGAGCUAAAUAUAAUCAAUUCUGUGAUUAGGAACUCAAAUUUUAGAAGUUGAUGACGUUAGUAAACUUCUAAUUGUCAUUUGUGAAACUUCCAAUUUUCCUUGCUGACUUAGCUAGUUACUGUUACUAAGGCAAGCAUUGAAGAGAGUUAACUAAGCAUUCCUAUUUGCCGUUUCCACACAACAAAAUGUGUCUGUCUCCUGGAUCUUUCUCUGCUCUAUGCUGUUUACUUACUGGUAACACCCACUUGACAAGUAAAGAACCUUUGCAUGGUCAUCACAAUGAAAGGAUAAGUUCUUACAAGAGUGAGAAUGCUAGAGCAACUAUUCCUUUUCACCUUCUACAGAAACCAGUGACUUUCGAGUAUGUGUACCACAAAAAGUUGUGUAAGGAGUGUAUUGAGAAUCUCCCAUGACUAAGUUGUCUGAGGAAGAGUUCAGUAAAUUUGUAUUCUUCAUGCAAAUUGAAGUCCUCUGUUUUGGUGCUAUUGCCUCUGAGUAUAAGGAAGGAUUUGUGAGUAAUCUUAUGUUGAAACAUAGUACUUCUGGUAAUGAUUAGAAAAUAUGUUUAGACCACACUUACAAGAAUUUCUCUUUAUUACAUUAGCUUUUCUUUUUGAAUUAAUUGAAGAAUUCUUAAAUUGUCCCACUUAUACGACAUAGCCAAAGAGUUUGGAUGAUCAUCUUUGGUCUAAAUUUUCACUAGCACUUGAACAGUCAGUGAAGAAUGGCAAGGGUGAGGACCAAAGGGUGAACUUUGCUUGCAGUAGUGCAUGUGCUUUCAGAAUCUUGCAUGCACCCUGUGAUCUUCACAGUUCCUGCAGCUGAUCAAGGUGUAGAGAGGGCAAAUGGCACAAAAUACUCUAAAUAAUUUCCUGCUGUGGUUGGUCUUUGGUUUCUGAGUGUCACCUGGCUUAGCUCUUUCAUUACCAGGCAUUUAGAGAGUAAAAAUUAGCACAGGAUAAACACUGGGUUUGCCUUCUAAGGUUUAAUUACUCAUCCUAAUAAAAGAAAGACAUCCUUGAAUCUGUGCAGAGUAUGUGAAACAGAGUCAGGGUAAAGUAUGUGAAACAGAAGGAACUUUGCUUGCUUGCUUUCUGACAUUUGGAUUAUCCAAAUGCUGGCAGACAUCAGAAGCAUUAUGUAAAGUGUUCUACAAAUUUGUUACUCAGAAAUAAUUUCGACUCUCUUAACUAAUUGAUAAAAUUGAAUCUAUCAUAGAAACUUGGCUUUGUAGAAUCCAACUCCCUCAGAAAAAGUUACCAAUUUAAGACGAUGUUUGAAAGGUUUUGUUAUAGCUUAUAAAACCUAGACAAUAAAAAGACUCUCUGUCUUUUCUCUAGGAAGUCUUUUUCUCUAGCAAUUUGUUUAAAGAACUAUCAGAGUGAUGAAUUCUCUAUAUAUAGGUUGCUUGUAUGCAUUCAAAUCUCUAGUCUGCUGAAAGCUGUUUACUCUUCUCUGGGUUCUUAGCAUCAAAUACGUAAUAAGUCACCAAUGAGUAUAUUUCUGAUUCUUUCAUUGAUCAGUUAGUUCAUCUGGACUAAUUGGGGAAAAAGCCAAAGCUAAAUAAUAGAAAAUUCUGAGUAAAAACCUUUUUAUGGGUAUCAUUUGUAAUUUAAAAGUCAAAGCAGAAAUAAAUUAAGCUAAUAGUUUAUAUCUUACUAGGCAUUAGAAAAUAUUUUUAUGAUAACUAUAACUAGUAGUUAUGUGUAAAUGAGUGCUGAAUUGAGGUAUUUGAAAGCAACUUAUUUUUAAGUAAUUUUAUCAUUUACAUAUAGUAUUAUAUUUAUGUAGAAAAAAUUAUAAAAACGUUUAUUUUAUCCCUUUUUAAGGGAUGUCAAAGUCUAUAUUCAAAAAAUUGAAUUAACCACUAUUUGUGCCUUGAAUACAUGGGAGGCAUUUUUUAUUGUUUACUUUGAGAUAAGAUAGAAACCUCUCAGUUUUAAAAAUAUUUUUCUUAACAGAGGGGAUAUCUACUCUUUAUAAAAAUCAGUGAUUGCAUAAUUUAAGGUAGUAUAAGGCAUGCUACCAAUUUAUAAAAACUAACCUGUGCCUUCUAUCCCAGCUGUUCUUACAGAAAUUAAGUUUCACUUUCUCAUCAGGCUAUGGUUGAGAAGUAUGUCUCAUUUAUAGUGCCUUCUGUGAUCUUAGGACAUGUGACUAAACUUGAAUAAAAGUUAAGGCUGUAUGACAUUUCUGGUACCUUCAUGAUGCAAAAUUUAAUCCCACACUACCAUAAAUAGAUGGCAGUGAGAUCUUCUGAUCUCAUAAGUGUAAUUUUUAUUUAUGAAAGAUUUUAGACUUAUCCACAUUUUAUUGGAAAGUGUUUUUGUGUUCUUUGCUUUGAUCUGUAGUUGUGUAAUAGAAAACAAACAACAAAAAAGCCAGCAUAACAAUAUUUUAGUAGGUUCUUUUCCUUAAGUAGAUACUGUAAUUUGCUUUUAGUGGUUGCAUUGGGGCCGGUGGACUUCAUUGUAUGGUAUUAUUUAUUAGGGGUUUAGCAAACAUCUAGAUGUAUUCAAAUGGCUAUGUCUUAGUAUCAGUGUGUUUUGAGAAUAAACUGUGUUAUGUUUGUUUAGCUCCCCACAUGCUUUUGGAGAAUAUACAAUUAAAAAGCUUAAAAACA